CUAAGCGGCGACGCGCGGGUGCUGGGAGGCCUUAGAACGCCGUGGCGUGCCGCAGGACGCGACGGCUGCAGAACAUCCGCCGCACCGCUGGGGGCCAACGUUGUCGGACCGAGGAGUCCGAGGUGGCGACUGAGUGAGAUACCCAGCUGUGCGGAGCUAGGACGCGGAACAUCCCAGAGGCCAGCAUCAACAUGAGGAGAGCCACUGUGGUCUGAAGAGAUGCUACUGCCUGGAGACUGGGGUCUUAACCUCCAGCCUGGCACUGAGCCACCUGCAACCUAGCAGCAGGUGACCUUGGCUCCCAGCCUGACUCAGCUGAACCUGGAUCCUGUGCAUAGGCAAGAGCUGACUCUGAGCCCUGGCCCAGCCAAGCUGACCCCUACACUAGACCCUACACACCGGAUGGAGCUGAUCCUGAGUACCAGCCCAGCUGAGCUGACUCUGGAUCCUGCGUGCCAGCCAAAGCUGCCCCUGGAUUCCACAUGCCAACCAGAGAUGACCUUCAAUCCUGGUCCAACUGAGCUUACCCUGGAUCCUGAACACCAGCCAGAGGAGACCCCAGCUCCUAGCCUGGCUGAGUUGACCCUGGAGCCUGUGCACCGCCGACCCGAGCUCCUGGAUGCUUGUGCUGACCUCAUCAAUGAUCAGUGGCCCCGCAGCCGCACCUCCCGCCUGCACUCCCUGGGCCAGUCCUCAGAUGCCUUCCCCCUCUGCCUGAUGCUGCUAAGCCCCCACCCCACACUUGAAGCAGCACCCGUUGUGGUGGGCCAUGCCCGCCUGUCACGGGUGCUGAACCAGCCCCAGAGCCUCUUAGUGGAGACAGUGGUGGUGGCCCGGGCCCUGAGGGGCCGUGGCUUUGGCCGCCGCCUCAUGGAGGGCCUGGAGGUCUUUGCUCGGGCCCGGGGCUUCCGCAAGCUGCAUCUCACCACCCAUGACCAGGUGCACUUCUAUACCCACCUGGGCUACCAGCUGGGUGAGCCUGUGCAGGGCCUGGUCUUCACCAGCAGACGGCUGCCUGCCACCCUGCUUAAUGCCUUCCCCACAGCCCCCUCUCCCCGGCCACCCAGGAAGGCCCCAAACCUGACUGCCCAAGCUGCCCCAAGGGGUCCCAAGGGACCUCCAUUGCCACCACCCCCUCCCCUACCUGAGUGCCUGACCAUCUCACCCCCAGUUCCAUCAGGGCCCCCUUCAAAAAGCCUGCUGGAGACACAAUAUCAAAAUGUGAGGGGGCGCCCCAUAUUCUGGAUGGAAAAAGACAUCUGAGGCCAUCCAGGGCAAGGAACUGUCUUUCUGGUUCAAUAGACUGCCCCGACAGUCUACAAGCCUCAGCCCACUGACCAUACCUCAGCCCCUAGCCCCUGGGGGGCAGCUUUAACCUGGGCAUGUUUCCUGGGUACCAGUGGGGCCAGGAGGUGGCUCUGGCUCAGAGCCGUCAGUGUGGCUGAAUAAAGGCUCUCUUGGGUA